GCACAGAGCUCCCUCCCAGGCCCGCGAACUUGGCCAUUCAGCCGCCGCUGUCCCCGCUGCGCGCCCUCGCGCCUCUGCCUGAGAAGCCAGGCGCUGUUCCCCCACCCCAGAAGAGGAUGGCAAAGGUGGCUAAGGACCUCAACCCAGGAGUUAAAAAGAUGUCCCUGGGCCAGCUGCAGUCAGCAAGAGGUGUGGCAUGUUUGGGAUGCAAGGGGACGUGUUCGGGCUUCGAGCCACAUUCAUGGAGGAAAAUAUGCAAGUCUUGCAAAUGCAGCCAAGAGGACCACUGCCUAACAUCUGACCUAGAAGACGAUCGGAAAAUUGGCCGCUUGCUGAUGGACUCCAAGUAUUCCACCCUCACUGCUCGGGUGAAAGGCGGGGACGGCAUCCGGAUUUACAAGAGGAACCGGAUGAUCAUGACCAACCCUAUUGCUACUGGGAAAGAUCCCACUUUUGACACCAUCACCUACGAGUGGGCUCCCCCUGGAGUCACCCAGAAACUGGGACUGCAGUACAUGGAGCUCAUCCCCAAGGAGAAGCAGCCAGUGACAGGCACAGAGGGUGCCUUUUACCGCCGCCGCCAGCUCAUGCACCAGCUCCCCAUCUAUGACCAGGAUCCCUCGCGCUGCCGUGGACUUUUGGAGAAUGAGUUGAAACUGAUGGAAGAAUUUGUCAAGCAAUAUAAGAGCGAGGCCCUCGGCGUGGGAGAAGUGGCCCUCCCGGGGCAGGGUGGCUUGCCCAAGGAGGAGGGGAAGCAGCAGGAAAAGCCAGAGGGGGCAGAGACCACUGCUGCUACCACCAACGGCAGUCUCAGUGACCCGUCCAAAGAAGUGGAAUACGUCUGCGAGCUCUGCAAGGGAGCGGCCCCUCCUGACAGCCCCGUGGUCUACUCGGACAGGGCAGGCUACAACAAGCAGUGGCACCCCACCUGCUUUGUGUGUGCCAAGUGCUCCGAGCCGCUGGUGGACCUCAUCUACUUCUGGAAGGAUGGUGCACCCUGGUGCGGCCGCCAUUACUGCGAGAGUCUGCGGCCCCGGUGCUCCGGCUGCGAUGAGAUAAUAUUCGCUGAGGACUACCAGCGUGUGGAAGAUCUGGCCUGGCACCGAAAGCACUUUGUCUGUGAGGGUUGUGAGCAGCUGCUGAGCGGCCGGGCGUACAUCGUCACCAAGGGUCAGCUUCUGUGCCCAACUUGCAGCAAGUCCAAACGCUCCUGAAGGGCUGCCCACCCACAGCCAGAAUCCACAGGAUCCCACCGAGAAGGAGAGCCAGGUGUGCCGAGACCAUCCUAAGGGUCCGAUGUGACAGCAAGCAAGUGAAAUAAACAAUGAUUUGCUUUUCAGUGAGAAUAUAUAUAUGAGAUAUAUAUAGAUAUAUAUUCUAGGUUGGGUGGUGGUAGAUCCUUGAGGGUCAGUAGUUUCAAAACCAAAAAUAUUCUAAGAAGUCUUAGGAUGGAGUUCCUUUUCUUUCUGUUGUUGUUUCCCAGCUACAACCAACUAAAGACACAAAUGGCGUUCUGCAAGGGGACUCUGGGAGGAGUUUUCCAGAAUGCAAUUCCGAGUGAGCAAAUCGCAUAGCUGUAGAAUGUGCGUGCUUUUUUGUGGACACAGGAGCUCCUCCAGGAGCAGGCUGGGAUCCCAACUAUCGCUUGUUGCCUCUUUUUCAAGUGGAAUUUGAAUUUUAAAUAAACAACUUUUUUUGGCAUGAUAAACAGAUCAAUAAAAGUUUUGUGAAUUCCACAUACACCCUUAUCUAAUUAUUUACACCAUGGCAGUGAUUUUGCAACACCCAGUGCUGGCAGAAAAUAUAGUAAAAUACUAAUGAGCCUCUCUAUCAAUGUAUCUCAUCAGACUUCCACUGGGAGUGUAGGCUUUGGGACAGAACCCCCGCCCCACCUGCCUAUUCCAGAUACUCCCAGAUCACUAAUGUAACAAAGGUAUCAUGUUUUAUGGUACACUGAAAAGUGGCCUGCUGGGAACUGAUGAGCUUCUCUUUAGCCAGGGACCUGACUCAGCUGCCCUCAGAGCCCAGGAAAAUAGCGAAUGAACCCCUCUGGGAAUAAGACCAGUACUGGGAAACCACUGAACAGGGGCCACCUAAGCUCCACCAAUGGGUGCCACAUGGGAUGUGGUGACUAAUGUGGGCAGAUCUUUAAAAAUACAGCACUUUUUCAAAUGCCAAAACAAUCAGAAACAAAAUUUUUUCAAUAAAAAUUAAUCUAAAAUUUAACAAUGCCACUUUUAUGAGAAAUCUCAAUUUUUAAUGUUGCCAACUAAACAUUGAAUGAGUCACGUAGAAUAGGUCUUUGGGCCAAAUUGUAUCUCCAUUUUAUGGUCUCUCUGAACAUUUUCAGCUCUUAAAUUAAUUUCUUUCCCACAGUUUCUAAGAAAAACAUAUUUUUCUACUGGGAGUAUAAGGAUGAAAAAGACACAAGUCCUAGGAGCUUACGGUCUGGUCGCCAGUGGUUUUCUUUCUUGAACUUCCUCAUCUGCUGCCAGUUUUCUUUAACCUCACCAUCCAAAUUUCACUCUGACCAUCUCGUACCUAGAAAACCCCCAUUCAUGUGCUUUAUAAGUUUCACCAAAGCCAUUGCUAUAUCCUCCCAAGGCAGUGGUUUUCUGCUCCCAGCUCCUUUCUCUAGUCACCCUCAGUUUCCUCGUCAUGUUCAUCUUCUCAAAGAUAAGUUUCAAGUGUGUCAUUUCCUUCACUCAAUCUCCAUGGCUCUUCAUUGCCUGCCAAGUUAACAACCAAGUCCUCAUGGACAUUUGAAUCCUUCCAAAACUUGGCUUAUGUCUUUCUGGCCUUGGAGCCCUUUAUUUCCCUAGAUUUCUAGUUCCCUAUUUCUUCCUAAGCAUGCAGAAGCUCCCUCUGAUCAAGCCCUUCCCUUUGCUUUUGCUAGUUGAAGACUGGCUACCUGAAGACCAACUCUGGCUGUUGAAAUUCUAUUCAUCCUAUAAGGUGCUUCUCAAGCAUAACCUGCUUCUCUGGCACUUUCCUGAAGCACCAGUGAAAUAUUCACCAAUUCAUCAUUCAUUCAUCCAUUCCACAAGUAUUUCAGUGAGCACGGCAAAGUUCCAAUUCCCAUGCUGAAUAUAGGGGAUGCGGGGUGCACAAAAAGAACAGUGACCCCUACGCCCAUAGAUGUUACGGUCUGUGGGGGAGAUGGGCCUCAAGCAAAUAUUCUCACAAGUCAAUGCAAAAUUACACUACUGUGCAUGCUAUAAAAGGAAGAUUUGUGUUACUAUAAUGCAUGUAAACUGGACUUAGGAAUAUCGAGAGAGGUGCCCCUGGGAAAGUGAUGCUUGAACUGGGCUGUAAAGGAUGAGUAGCCUUGCCAGGCAUAGUGGCUCAGGCCUGUAUUCUCAGCACUUUGGGAGGCCAAAGCGGGUGGAUCACUUGAGCCUAGGAGUUCGAGACCGGCCUGGGCAACAUGGCAAAACUCCACCCCUACAAAAAAUACAAAAACUAUCUGGCAUGGUGGCACACCUGUAGUAUCAGUUACUCUAGAGGAUAACCUGAGCCCAGUAAGUCAAGGCUGCAGUGAGCUGUGAUCAUGCCACAGCACUCCAGCCUGGGUGACAGAGUGAGACCCUGUUUCCAAAAAAAAAAAAAAAGGAUAGGUUGCCUCUAAGUUGGCAAAGAGAGGAAGGACAAUGGUUAAAGAUGGAUACAUGAAUGCAUGUGCAAAGGCCCUGUGGUGGAAGCCCCACCAGUUUAUUCAACACCUAUUUGCUGGUGUUGGAGAUACAGUGGUGAACAUGGCCCAUGGAUGGAACUGAAAGAAAACUGGUGUGGCAGGAGCACAGAGCAUGGUGAGGAGGGUGGGCCUGGGGCAUGAGAGGCAGGCAUGGCCAGCCUGCUCCAGUUCUGGGGCAAUUCAAAAGACUGGUCUCUGUUCUAGGAGCAAGGGGGAGCCUUCAAACAGCUUUAAGGAGGGGGUGGUGAUGGCUGGACAGGGAGAUCAUGAGAUACGUCAUCUCUUCUCUGUUGAAACCCCAGCACAAUGCAUGAUUGACUUGGUCCACUGGGUCACACCAUCAUGGAUGGGCAUUAUCUCCCACAACAGUCCCCAUGGGGCACCACCCAGCACCUGCCCCUGCCUUUCUCAUGUCUAUUAAUGACACCCACCCUUGCAUUUGGAGCACCUGAAUCAUCUCUGCCACUUGCCUUCAUAUCUGAUGGGUCACUCAGUCCAGUCCUUUCUCUCCAUCCUCGCUUUCACUCCAUCCCCAAAGUCAUAUCUCACCUUGAACAUUUUCUGCUCAGACUGACAAGUCUCCCCGACGGGAACUCACCCUCUCCACCCACCACUUCCAGAUGAAUUGCUCAGAAACACACCCUCAUCUUGCACUCUCCUCUUCAAGAACAAUCAGGGGCUCCCUGUUGCACACACAGAAAAAAAUUGAAACUGUUUUACCUUGCAGUCGAGUUUCUUAUUUUUCCUGCCCCAACCCUCCUUCCUUCCUGUUAUCCUUUCAGAAGCCAAAUGGGCAGUUUACAGUCACAGUGUGUGCCCCUGCUUUCCUCACCUCUGUACCAUCACUCACGCUGUGCUUUUUGCCUGCAAUUCCCCACACUGUGUUUAAUUGCUGCCUCUGCUGGGGGGCUGCAAUAGCUGAGUGGGAUUCUGUACCAGAAUUGGAAAGAUCCAUGUUAACUCUUGCCUGAUUCUAUCUCCCAUGUCAGCAGGAAGAGGGGCUGCCAUCCCCACCCCUCCCACUCUCUAGGAAGACUUUCCUCCCUCACCCUUCCCUUGGGGUGUUUUAGGUGCCCUUUAUCUGUAAGUUCAUAAUAUCCCAGGCUUACAGUAAUUCUUCCAAGGCCUUUAUUGUGCUAUAAUUAUUUAUUCAUGAAAGCCUUCCCCUAUGAACUUCUAAAGAAUAAUCGUAUUAUCUUUAUUUCCCCAACUCUUAGUACAAAUCCUGGCAACUAAAUGAAAGAACAAACAACCUGGGGUUCUGGGAUGGUUCGUCUUUGCUGAUGGCACUGUGUUCCAAAAUGGCCAAGGUCAAAUAUAAAAAUUUCAGACUGAGGUAGACACUGCUGGCAGCCUACACAUUGCCACCACACCCCACUUCCUUCUUCCUAGUGGCAAGGAAGCAGUGGGUGGAGAGGGUGAGUUCCUGUCAGGGAGACUUGUCAGUCUGAGCAGAAAAUGUUCAAAGUGAGAUAUGACUUUGGGGAUGGAGACAAAGGGAGGAUGGAGAGAAACGACUGGACUGAGAGAAGAGCCCACUCCCCUUUAUGUAAAUUGGCUUUGCCAACCUGGUCUGCAGCUGGAGAAAGGCCAUGCGCCUCUAUUACCAGCCAGUGGGGCUUCCGCCUUAGGAGGGUCUUAGAAAAGUGUUUUUCCUUAAUGAAAGGAGAUACUGUGCAGUAAAUAGCCCUGCUGUUGUUUUCUUUUCUUUUGAUAGAAUGUCAAACUUACGAAAAAAGUUACAAGAAGAGAACAAAGAGCUAUUAGAGGGUGUUGCUGACACAAUGCUUUAUCACUCUUGAAUAUUUUCGUGUGUAAUUCCUACAAAUAAGGACAUUCUCCCACAUAGCCACAAUACAACCAUCAAAAUCAGGAAGUUAACGCUGAUGUGUUUCUACCAUGUAAUCCUCAGAUCCAAUUCAAGUGUCACCAGCUGUCCCAAUAAUGUCUUUUAUAACAAAAACAUUCAGUCUAAGAUCACUCAUUCUAUUUAGUUAUCUUGUCUAUUCUUCAAUUUGGAAGUGUUCUUUGUUCUUUCCUGAAUGUUCAUGACCUUGACAUCUUAGAAGAUUAAAGGUUAUUUAAAGUUGUUGAGUUAAAUAUCCAUUAAAUUAGGUUUGUCAGAUAUUUCCUCGAAAUUAGAUUCAGCUUAUGCAUUUUUUGGAAGGAAUACCACAGAAGUGAUGUUGUUUUCUUUCUGUUGCAUCCAAUCAGAUGAUACAGGAUUUUGAUUUGUUCCAUUACUGUUGACAUGAAUUUUGAACAUUUGAUAAUGCCAGUAUCAGCCAGAUUUUUCCAUUGUAAAGUCAUUCCUUUGUCCUUUGUAUUUAAUAAGUAUGUUUAGGGACUUUGAGACUAUGUCAAUGUCCUGUUCUUCAUCAAAAUUCCACUCACUCAUUCUUAGUAUUCAUUGACGUUUACUGAUCGAACUAAUUAUUAUUAUGAUAGUUGCCAAAUGUUGGUUUUUCUAAUUCAAUCAUUUCUUUAGUGUUUAUUAGCAUUCUACUAUAAGGAAAAGCACUAUCUUCUCCCCAUUUAUUAAUUCACAUAUUUACAUCAGCUUGGAGUUAUUGAUUUCUAUUUUAUUAAAUAGUUUAUAAUUGAUUACCAUCCUUAUUUAUUUUAAUGCUCAAAUUGUCCCAAAUUAUGGCCAAAGAAAGCUCCUUCAAACUGGUUGCUAUGUCCUUUUGACAUGGCCCAUCAUUCUUUAAACACAUUUUACAUCUGGCACAAUAACGUGCUACAUACCCAUCUUGUAUUUUUCCUGCCCCAUCUUUGAAAUCAGCCAUUCUCAAGGGGUUCCUUCUUAAUCUGGCUGUUGUUGUGUUGGAACUCCUGGUACCAUCUUAGAACCUUAAGGAGACAAGCGAACCAAGCCAAUAAGCUUUCCAUGAUGCUGCUUAGAGUUAAACAGAGCCCAGGUACUAAGUUAUGUCAUGGAGACAGUGAACUAACCUCUGGACUGCUUGCUACAUGAGACAAUUGAUUUUCUUAUUUUCUAUGUAGGGUGGUACAUUUCCUCAUUUUGAGAUAUUUCUUCAACAUAUAGCUUUUCAUUAGUGGGGAUUUUGUCAAUUAUAACCAAAAACAAUGUGACGGAUACCCAAGAUGUUUCAUGUUGUAGCUUGGGUGAAUUACACAUUUCUGAAGCCAUUACACUUCCUAGUUUAUUUGGAUUUAAGUUGACAAAUAAAAAUUGCAUAUGUUUAUGGUCUAUAACAUGGUGUUUCGAUAUAUGUAUACAUCGUGGAAUGGCUAAAUCAAGCUAACAUAUCCAUUACCUCACAUAGUUAUUUUUUGUGGUGAGAACAUUUUAAAAAUAUUGUCUUAGCAAUUUUCAAUCAAGCCUGUCCCAUGGAGACACAAGCAAUAGUGACAUGAGCACUUGACUCGCUGGGUUAUCAGGCUUUGGCUCCAAAUGUUUGGCUUCAAAUAUGAAAAAGUUACAUGAAAGAUGAAACUAUGCAAUGGCAUGGCUGUUGGUCAUUCACAUCUCUCUCUGCCAAGAAUGGGGAUGACGCUGUUGAAGGAAGAAAUGUGUUUUCUCCUUUUUCUCAAGUGAUAUUUGCCUUAGGUCAGAUUCUACUAGUUUAAAGCAAAACGAUCUCCUGGUCUGAUUCCUUUGGGUCUCUAAUAAUGGAAACUGCAAGGAUCAGCAUAAAGUGUUCCUUUGUUCUGACGUUGGUAUAACAUUGCUUCUUGAAAAAUGAAAGUAUUUGGACAUACAGACAGAAGCAAUAUUAUUCAGGUCUUCCUUGUUGCAAGUGAGGGAAAUCCAAUUAAAACUGGUUUAAACCUAAAAAAAAAAAAAAGAAGAAAAGAAAAGAAAAAAUAUGAGAGGGGUUUUGCUUUCUGGAAUCUGCUUUCUAGUCAGAAAGUGCAGAAGAAGGGCUAGCUUCAGGAACAAUUGGAUGCAGUAGUUCAAAUCACAAGUUAAGUCUCUGCUUCUUUUCUCCAUCUCUCUUCUGUCUUCCUCCACACUGGCUUUAUUCUUAGGUAGGCUUACCCAGAUAGUCAUAAACACAGCCACCAGUGGCAGCUGGGCUCACUUUUGUCCUUGGAGCCAGUGAGCCCAUGAAAAAGGAGCUUCUCUUUCUGGAGCUUCCCAGGGGUAACUUUGAUCAGCCAACAAGGGUCAGUCCUAUGCUUAUCCCUUGACCAAUCUCUGUGCCCAGAGGGCAGGGUACUCUGAUUGGCAAUACCUUCAUCGUGGGCCAACCACUGUGGGGAAGGGGGAGGGAUUAGAAAAGACAGCCACACCCAAAUCUCAUGAAGCAGUCCCCUUUAUUUUAAAAAAGUCCCUGUGAGAGCAACAGGAGCAAAGCAUGGAGAAGAAGCAAUCUUGGAGAAGCUGGAAGAGAACUGACCCAAAGAAUCCAAGAGACUAAGACUGUGCAGGGUUGGGGAACGGAAGCUCACACAGGAGGCCUGGACAGAGCUGCAGCAGAGCCAGGAGAGAAGCCAAGUGGCACAGCUCAUCUUGAAGUAAUUAUAAUGCCACUAAAAUUCUCAUUUGUAUUAAUUUUUUUUAAUUACUGGCAAGAUAAGGCAAAUGUUUUUAAAGGCCUAAAUAAAAUGAUAUUCCCUGAA